GCGAGACCGGAGGGGUCCGAGCAGCGGCUGCGGAGCCGGAGCUGGGCGAGGGCGGCUGCGGUCCCGGCGGCGGCGGCGGCGGCGGCAGCUGCGGCGGGAGAAGAUGGUGGCGCUGGAGGCAGCAGCGGCUGGAGCGGAGCUUUAUUCCCAGGCUUGGCACCAGCGCUGUCACUAGCGCCGCCUGCUCCCGCGGGCCCGCGGACCCAGCUGUCAGGCAAGGCUUGGGUUUGGAAAACAUGCACGUUGGAGAGAAGGAAAGGAGAGCUGGGAUUAGAAUCCACCAUCCACGCCUAUCUGAGAGUGGGAGAAUUACUUUGUCAAUGUAAGAAGUGAUAAAAACCGGAAUAGACUUGUCUUAUUAGGCUGACGUUGUUCUUGUUGAUUUAUUAACUUGAAUUUCUUUCUUCAGAACAUAGUCACAAACAAACCAAGAGGGAAAAUGGAAGUUCUAAUCAUAGGCUUUGGUAAUCAAUCGCCGUGGGGAUGAAAUGUUAUUUAAUUUAUAGCCUGUUCAUGUUUGUAUAUGGCACUUACCAUGUUAUAUGGGGAGAGAGAUACACAAUCUAGCCCAUAACAGUGAAGAUAUAAUGUGUUUGUUGGGUGAGAGGUAACAAAAAAAAGACAAAGGGGGCUAUUCUCUCAAAGUGUCUCCAAAAGUUCCUUGAAAAAGCUGCAAACUGAUUAGAAGGUAGGUUUUUUCCUAGUACAAAAUAAUUUACUUAGUCCCUUUUCAGAGGAUCAUUCUAUCAUGUUAUAUCUGUUUAUAAAUCUCUAAAUAUCAGAAAAAGAGAUGCUUAAAGAGGAUCAAACUAUUUUGGGAGAGUCACUUUGAAUUCAAGAGAAAGGAUAUAUUACAGUAUUACCAGCUGUCUCAAAUAUGAUCCUAUAUGAUCAUGAGGAUCCAAAUAGAUCCUUAACUCCCCCAGAUUGUGACUUCUUUGUAUUUUCUCUGGGAAUCUUUGAACACUGGGCAGCUGGCCUCUGCAAUCACACUGUCAUUCUUUUCUUGCACAUGUCUCCAUCCUCAGCCACUGGAGGUUGUGUCUCACUCUCAUGCAUGUCAUCACUGCCUGGCACAGAGUCGGCACUCAGUACACUUUAUAUUAAAGUGAAUACUUCCAUCGCAUAAAGCAAGUGACUGUUAUUAAAAUGUGUUCAGUAGCCUUUAGGUCCUAAACUCUGGGCAAGUUCUCAUUGCUCCAGAUGACUCCUGCACCACCUCUCUUUUGCUAGAAGGAGAAGCAAUGAGUUAAGUGCCUUCUCAAGCUUCUUAGAUCCCUGAUUAAUAUUCUCUGAUUCUCUGUCUUGGAAUGCAUUUAAAAUCUCUGCCUCGAUUCUGACCUACCUGGCAUGGGAACAAGAAUUUACAAUGUUACUCACCCACAAUGAAGAUUACAUGCCUGGCAAUUUGAUUUAAUUAUUUGUGGAGCUUAAUUCAGGCUGUUCAUAUCUGCCUAGGCAGGAAAAAAAAAACUCUAGCAAGUUUUUGGGCCAUUUUUGAAUCAGUAUUAUUGCAGAAGAAGGCAAGAAAUUUUUUUCCAUUUUAAGCCUGGCAUUCACCCCUAUAACAGAGUUUAUUUCACAAGAAGAAUGUUAAGUCUUGCAGACAAAGUUUUCUGUUUCUUCAUGUUAGUAGAAAUGUGUAACGUUGCCUCAGUCACCUUCAACCAUAUGCAUAAGAGAAGUAGAUAUUUUUUUGAGGGUUUCUCAGUCUCGGCACCAUUGGCAUUUGGGGCUGGACAAUUCUUUGUGUGUGGGACAUUGUAGAAUGUUUAGUAGCAUUCCUGGCUUCUACUCACUAGAUGCCAGUAACACACACACACACACACACACACACACACACACACACACACUCACACGUGACAACCAAAAAUGUCUCCAUAUAUCAAGGGAAGGGUGCAGGGGAGAGGCAAAAUAGCCCUCCUGUACACUAGAAUGUAUGGAAAUAAAUACAUACAAGACAUUCUCACACACUCUCUCAAAUAGCUUUGGCAAAUUCUGUUUGGCUUUCACUUACGUGAAAAUCACUUCUUUUAGAAGACUUUUUCAGUUCAGGGAUGUGAUGUGGGGUGGGGUGUGUGUGUUGGUGUGUGAAAAACCACACCUGAAUGAAAAAUGCAGCCUCCCUAGGAAGGUGACCAAGUUAACUUUCCUUUUCAGGGAAGAAGCACCACAGGAGGUCAAACGGAAACCCUAGCGGAUGCCUGUUCCAUAGCUAACCCAGUGGAGCAAAAUGAGAGCGCAGUGAGCCGGGCCCAGCUUCUCUCCUAGCCGUUCCGACUCCCACCAUGAACCACUUGGAGGGGUCUGCGGAGGUGGAGGUGACCGACGAGGCGGCAGGUGGGGAGGUGAACGAGUCGGUGGAGGCCGACCUGGAGCACCCCGAGGUGGAAGAGGAACAGCAGCAGCCGCCGCAGCAGCAGCACUAUGUGGGCCGCCACCAGCGCGGGCGAGCCCUCGAGGACCUCCGCGCCCAGCUCGGCCAGGAGGAAGAGGAGCGCGGGGAAUGCCUGGCGCGCUCAGCCAGCACGGAGAGCGGCUUCCACAACCACACGGACACCGCCGAGGGCGACGUGAUCGCCGCGGCCCGCGACGGCUACGAUGCGGAGCGCGCGCAGGACCCCGAGGACGAGAGCGCCUAUGCUGUGCAGUACCGGCCCGAGGCCGAGGAGUACACGGAGCAGGCAGAGGCCGAGCACGCCGAGGCCACGCACCGCCGCGCGCUGCCCAACCACCUGCACUUCCACUCGCUGGAGCACGAGGAAGCCAUGAAUGCGGCCUACUCAGGCUACGUCUACACGCACCGGCUCUUCCACCGCGGUGAGGACGAGCCCUACUCCGAGCCCUAUGCCGACUACGGCGGCCUCCAGGAGCACGUGUACGAGGAGAUAGGGGACGCGCCCGAGCUGGACGCACGCGACGGCCUGCGGCUCUACGAGCAGGAGCGCGACGAGGCGGCCGCGUACCGCCAGGAGGCCCUGGGCGCGCGGCUGCACCAUUACGACGAGCGCUCCGACGGCGAGUCCGACAGCCCCGAGAAGGAGGCCGAGUUCGCGCCCUACCCGCGCAUGGACAGCUACGAGCAGGAGGAGGACAUCGACCAGAUAGUGGCCGAGGUGAAGCAGAGCAUGAGCUCGCAGAGCCUCGACAAGGCAGCCGAGGACAUGCCUGAGGCCGAGCAGGACCUGGAGCGUCCCCCUACCCCGGCCGGGGGUCGCCCCGACAGCCCCGGGCUGCAGGCGCCGGCGGGGCAGCAGCGGGCGGUGGGCCCCGCGGGCGGCGGCGAGGCGGGGCAGCGGUACAGCAAGGAGAAGCGCGAUGCCAUCUCGCUGGCCAUCAAGGACAUCAAGGAGGCCAUCGAGGAGGUGAAAACCAGGACCAUCCGUUCGCCUUACACCCCCGACGAGCCCAAAGAGCCCAUCUGGGUCAUGCGCCAGGACAUUAGCCCCACCAGGGACUGUGACGACCAGAGGCCGAUGGACGGAGAUUCUCCGUCUCCUGGCAGCUCCUCCCCCUUGGGUGCAGAGUCAUCAAGCACAUCUCUUCACCCCAGUGACCCUGUGGAAGCGUCCACUAAUAAAGAGUCAAGAAAAAGCUUGGCUUCAUUCCCAACCUACGUUGAAGUUCCGGGACCCUGCGACCCCGAAGACUUGAUCGAUGGAAUCAUUUUUGCCGCCAAUUACCUUGGCUCCACUCAGCUGCUCUCAGACAAAACUCCUUCCAAAAACGUGCGCAUGAUGCAGGCCCAGGAAGCCGUAAGCAGGAUCAAGAUGGCCCAGAAAUUAGCCAAAAGCAGGAAGAAGGCUCCUGAAGGCGAAUCUCAGCCAAUGACUGAAGUGGAUCUCUUCAUUUCUACCCAGAGAAUCAAAGUGCUGAACGCCGACACACAGGAGACAAUGAUGGACCACCCUCUGAGGACCAUUUCCUACAUUGCGGACAUUGGGAACAUCGUUGUGCUGAUGGCCCGCCGGCGGAUGCCUCGCUCCAACUCCCAGGAGAACGUGGAAGCGUCCCACCCAUCCCAGGAUGGGAAAAGGCAGUACAAGAUGAUCUGCCACGUCUUCGAGUCUGAGGAUGCUCAGCUGAUUGCACAGUCCAUCGGACAGGCAUUUAGCGUGGCAUACCAGGAAUUCCUCAGGGCCAAUGGGAUUAACCCCGAAGAUCUCAGCCAGAAGGAGUAUAGUGACCUGCUCAAUACCCAGGACAUGUACAACGAUGACCUGAUCCACUUCUCCAAGUCGGAAAACUGUAAAGAUGUUUUCAUAGAGAAGCAGAAAGGAGAAAUCCUAGGUGUGGUGAUUGUGGAGUCUGGCUGGGGAUCCAUCCUCCCCACCGUGAUCAUUGCCAACAUGAUGCAUGGUGGCCCUGCGGAGAAAUCUGGGAAGCUGAAUAUCGGUGACCAGAUCAUGUCCAUUAAUGGCACCAGCCUGGUGGGCCUGCCUCUGUCCACCUGCCAGAGCAUUAUUAAGGGCUUAAAGAAUCAGUCCCGAGUCAAGCUGAAUAUCGUGAGAUGUCCUCCGGUGACCACCGUGUUAAUCAGAAGACCAGACCUUCGCUACCAGCUCGGUUUCAGCGUCCAGAAUGGAAUUAUCUGCAGCCUCAUGCGAGGGGGAAUAGCUGAGAGAGGAGGCGUCCGUGUGGGGCACCGGAUCAUUGAAAUCAAUGGACAGAGCGUCGUGGCCACCCCCCACGAGAAGAUCGUCCACAUUCUCUCCAAUGCUGUUGGGGAGAUUCAUAUGAAGACAAUGCCAGCCGCGAUGUACAGGCUGCUGACGGCCCAGGAGCAGCCUGUUUACAUCUGACCGCGGCCACACGCGGUGGCAUGCAUGGAGGACUCUCCUCUUCGUGGUUGUGUUUCUCGUGCUGCAUCCCUGUGUCCACUGAGACUUUCCCCUCUCGCGCCCAGCAUUUGGUUUUACACAGGAAGAGAAGAAUCCACAAGGACCUCUUUACUCUCUCCGAUUUGCUUUUUUUUUUUUUUUUUUUUCAAUACCAGGGAAGUUUCGUAUGCACUCCCUUGAGGAUGGAGAGCAGCCAGCACCCACCUGGUACUGACCCAGGACCAUCCUGGAGGGCUUUCUGGGUGUGUCCAGGGGGUGGGCUGUCACUGCUUGAGGGAGAAUCCUCCCUUCCCAGGAGGUGCAGACUUCUUAAAAGGAGCUCGCGGGGCAGCAAAGCAGCUGAUUCAGCAGUGCCUAAAACCCAGUUGCUGAUCCCUGCUCUCUGAGUUUAUCUGUGGGAAUGUGGUAGUACCCAGGGCCAGCCCACGUCAUUAAGGUUAUGCACUGCCUGCCAUGUAGUUGGGGCACCAUACAUUAUUUCUUCCCAGAAUCUCUGAGCCAACCUUAAACCUCUUCUAUUGCUAGUUCUAAUUUCAACGUAUGUGUGUUUUCUAAUACGAGCCUUCUCACCCCAGGAUAAAAGGGGAAAUAACUGCCUUGGGCAAGGACACCAUAGUGUCACAGAGAGCUUGGCAAUUCAUGGGGCAUCUGAAGCUUUACCAGGUUGUCCUCAAGUUAUCAACCAUUAGAUAAACACAGGCAGGUACUGUCUGCUUCUCUCUCUCUCACACACACACACACACACACAGUCCCAUUUGCAUAUCACCCUUCCCUGCUCCCACCACCAGUGAGACAAGCUGAAGAUUAGGCACACAGAUCCCCUGGAAACCCACCUCUCUGGAAGGCCCCUUCCCUGGCAGGUGGCCAGGCAGGCGGGGGCUGCUCAGCCUCAUCCUGAGAGACCUGCCCUCUCUGCGCUGAGGCCCAGCCCCUCCAGCACCACUUUGGCUUAAAGCAUCCUCCUCCUGGACUCCCCUCCCUGCCGAACACACAUCCCAGGAGUCUGGGAAGGAGGGACUGUUCCCAAGAAGGCAAGCUGCAGGUGCAAUUGCGUCUUGUUUUCUGGCCCAAGGCAAGACCAACUUUCUUCUCUGCUCAGGGCCACUAGGCGGAUGUGAUAUUGGAAAGGCCAGAAUAGUACAUAAACCACAAAAUUAAGGAGACAAUAGCAACCUCAAGUUAUGCCUCAGAAUCCCCAGAUGUGGUCCAUAAACACCCUCUUGCUGCCUUGUGGGCCUGAGAGCAUUUUUGGCUGGUGUGGAAUUGUUCCGUGUUUUCAUCAGGUGCCUCAUAUUUAUGCUUCCGUCUCAGUUCAGUGUAGAUGUUUUAGUAAUAUUAUAAUUCUGAGCCAGUUUUCACUUGGUCCAAAGAGCAUUUUGUGUUCAUGUGAGGUGUGAUUUGGCUUUGCUUUUGUUUUGUUUCAUUCAUGACCUCAGUAGAGACAGGGGAAGAGAAACUAUUAUAUUUUGUAAUUAAUAUAGUCCCUGUUCUCUGCAUCCGAGAUAUUUAUGUUGUGUCUAUGGAAAUAGGAACUCAGUGAGCAAAUGGUGGGUAGCAUGUAUUUAUAGAGAGAAUGGAGGGAUUCUAAGGAGGGAGCAAAGUGACUAUAACAAGAUUAGGGACAAGAGACUUCAACCAGAGAGUUCUGUGAUCAAUUCCCCGAGAUCUCUGCAUCUUCUGAGUUUUCUGCUUAGAAUCAGGGAAGCUCAGUGCUUGACAGGAACGAGCAGUGGCACUCUCAGUUUCACUGUGUUACAAAGGAGCCCUGAGGAAGGGAGGCCGCUGGCUGCCCAGGUGCCCUGGGGGGAAAGGGACUUCUGCUGCUGCAGAGAGUGGCACCCGGUGGGGCCAGGGGCUCUGGGAUGGUCCGUAAAGCUCCCCAGGACUUCUUUGAAGGAUGCUUUACAGAAUGUUUCUGGGAGACCAGCCUCAAGGUCAACCCAUCACAAACGUGAGGACCAGGAAGGAACCAUGGCCAGGGUUCUCCAUUUGCUGUAGAGUAUCUGGUGAUACAGUGAGACACUAAAGAGUCAUCAGCCAGUUCAUCUUUCCUCUGCCAAUAAGAGUGGAUAGAACAGGAAUGAAGUGUUACUGGUGGUAUUUCAGGCAUCAGGAGCCUUGGAAAAUCAUCGUAGGGGCCCAUGCCUGUCUGUCCCUAGGCACCUGGGCAGUGCCACAGAGGCCCGCCCACGACUGGCCAGGGGACAGAACUCCAGUAGUGCAUCCCUGUACAACCUGCACAUAACGGUUAUGUAUGUUCACCUAAAGGAGAGAAUAUACUUUCUAUUCCUAUUGCACAAAAACCUUGUAAACUUUGAGAGGUGCUGAAAAAGCCAAUUCUGCAAGCUCUCCUAGAGGACUGACAUUGUAACAUUAGAGUGAGAAGAUUUCUCUGCCACAUUCUUUUGUGUUAAUCCAGGUGUGUCUUCACACCCAGUGAGUGGAAGUUGCUGGAGCUCGGUACAGGUCCACCCAGCUGAAGUGGGUUCUUUUUCCCACUACCACUGGGGCAAGGGAGUGAGCCUAGGUAUGGUCACCUCAGCAGCCACAGUCUUAAAAGCAAGUCGCUAGAUUUUUUGAAAGUCCCAAGAGAAGUGGUGGUCUUCCCUUCUGUCAUCCCAGUAUAUAUAGUUAUACAUGUAAAUAUCUAAAUACCCCAUGUAAUGGGAAGGCUAUGUACAGGGCAGCCUUCCCAAACGCUGUGAGGGCACAGAGCUGCUGUGGCUGCUCCACCAGGGUGUGCUGGUGGCUCAGCUUUGGGGUUGGACUCCCACGUUCACCUCCCCCUCCUGGUCCAGGCAGAGGCACCAGAACCCAUCCUGCCUUUUCUCCAGUGUGAGCAUUUCAGGGAGCCACCAUCAGCCUUGGGUUCAUGAGAGGAAGAAACCCCCAAAGACCAAUGCCUGGAGCCCACUUCUCCAGCGACACCUUCCCUCGCCAGAGCAGGCUCCUAGGAGUGCAUGGCAGGGGUGCCGGGUCCCUGUGCACGGGUUUGCUUUCUGAACAUUGCCCAUCAACACCGCCUUCAGGGAGUCCCAGAGUAACCUACUACCUCCCCCAUCGCUCCUCUGCCCCCCUCACCCUGUGGGCACCAACACCUCCCGCACACAGAUGAAAACCAUCUACAGAGCCCUUCCCGGGUCCCUCGACCCAGUGGUGUAGCCGUUACCAAUGUUUACAACCAGGGGCCGCCCCUCCUUAGAUGUGUUUACUCGCAUUCACAGGCCACCUGUUGGUUUGAGUUUCAUGUGUCUCCUUCCCUGGCCUAGGUUGACUUGAGCACACAACUCGAUCUUUCUUCCCCUCCAUCAAGGCAGUGUGUGAGGACUGUGUGGGAAUGACAUUUCUUGUACAUACUUAGCACAGCACCUAGAGUAUGAACUUGUACUAUUGUUCUGUAAAGAGGGUGAAAUAGAGCUUAUUGUAAAGUGUCGGGAGAAGUAUAGUAUUGUAUUUGUAACAAUAUCGUUCUUUGUAUACACAAAACUCAAUGAUCUAUAUAUAAAUAUAAAUAAAUAUAUAAAUAAAAUAUAUCUACACGUGAGCCUGGAAUGUGGACACCGCACACCCACUGAAUGUACUUCCUUGACAGUCUGGUCACUGGUCCCUCCCUCCCUCCCUCCUCCGUCCCGUGGCCACAGUCAUCCAGUUUGGGGUUGUGAUGUAUUUACUGUGCUAUCUAUCUUCCUUUAUUUAACUGAACGCUAAUGUCUGUAUAAGAGUUGCUGCAACAAUAAACAAGAACUUCACCUCUUG